AGAGGCCGACCACGUGUACUGUGGAGACUGUCAAAGUCUCCCGGAGCCCAAUUUCCGGAAGCGGUGAGUUCUGAAAGAAGUUCCUGCACCGUAGUUUCCCAAGUCUGCGAAUCCCCAACCAUGAGCGCCUCGGGCGUACUGUCCUUUACCCAGCAAGGAUGGGAGCAGGUGCUGGCCAAAGUGAAACGGGCUGUGGUUUACCUGGACGCCGCCUGCGCCGAGAGCCUGCACUGGGGCUGCGGAUCCACCCGUCUCCUGGAGGCGGUGGGGGGUCCUGACUGUCACCUGCGAGAGUUCGAGCCCGACGCAAUUGGUGGUGGAGCCAAGCAGCCCAAGGCAGUGUUUGUGCUGAGCUGCCUGCUGAAAGGCCGGACCGUGGAGAUCCUACGGGACAUCAUCUGCCGCAGUCACUUCCAGUAUUGUGUGGUGGUCACAACCGUGAGCCACGCUGUCCACCUCACAGCUAAUCAUGUCCCAGCGGCGGCAGCGGCCGAGAUGGAGGGGCAGCAGCCGGUGUUCGAGCAGCUGGAGGAGAAGCUGUGUGAAUGGAUGGGCAACAUGAACUACACGGCCGAGGUGUUCCAUGUCCCGUUAUUGCUUGCCCCUGUUGCUCCCCACUUUGCCUUGACUCCAGCUUUUGCAUCCCUUUUCCCACUGCUACCCCAGGAUGUGCACCUCCUUAAUAGCGCCCGACCGGACAAGAGGAAGCUGGGAAGCCUGGGUGAUGUGGACUCCACUACGCUAACCCCAGAGCUGCUGCUGCAGAUCAGAUGCCUAGUGUCAGGCCUCAGUUCUCUGUGUGAACAUUUAGGAGUACGGGAGGAGUGUUUUGCUGUAGGUUCCUUAAGUCAGGUCAUCGCUGCGGAUCUGGCCAAUUAUGCCCCUGCAAAGAACAGGAAGAAGACUGCUGCAGGCAGGGCAUCAGUGGUUUUUGUGGACAGAACCCUGGAUCUCACAGGAGCAGUUGGACAUCAUGGAGACAACUUAGUAGAGAAGAUCAUUUCAGCACUUCCCCAGCUCCCAGGCCACACAAAUGAUGUGAUGGUUAACAUGAUAGCGCUCACUGCACUCCAUACUGAGGAGGAAAAUUAUAAUGUGGUUGCACCAGGCUGUCUUUCACAAUCCAGUGACACCACAGCCAAAGCCCUAUGGGAAGCUUUACUGAACACUAAGCACAAAGAGGCAGUGAUGGAAGUUCGGAGACAUCUAGUGGAAGCGGCAAGCAGAGAAAACCUGCCAAUCAAGAUGAGUAUGGGGAGAGUCACACCGGGACAGCUCAUGUCCUAUAUUCAGCUCUUCAAGAACAACCUCAAAGCUCUAAUGAAUCAUUGUGGCCUCCUCCAGCUUGGACUGGCCACAGCUCAAACGUUGAAACACCCACAGACUGCCAAGUGGGACAACUUUCUGGCUUUUGAAAGGCUCCUUCUUCAGAGCAUUGGGGAGUCAGCAAUGUCCGUUGUGUUAAAUCAGCUGCUGCCCAUGAUUAAGCCUGUAACCCAGAGAACCAACGAGGACUACAGCCCUGAGGAACUGCUGAUCCUUCUCAUAUAUAUUUAUUCUGUCACUGGAGAGCUCACGGUAGACAAAGACCUGUGUGAAGCAGAAGAAAAAGUCAAGAAAGCAUUGGCUCAGGUCUUCUGUGAGGAAUCUGGAUUGUCACCUUUGCUGCAAAAAAUUACGGAUAUAAAACAGAUAGCAGCAGCAUCAGAACUUUGGGUGAGUUACCUCACUAUUUCACACAGUAAGUUUUCAUUUAACUUGUUUUUAUUCAUCUUCUCUCUCCUUGUUUUUCAUAUGUGAUUUGAAUGUUUCGCACGUUUAUUUCUAGUGGGUGAAGAAAUAUGUGGUACCAUUGCAUAACUACCUCCACCCCUGGAUAAUUGUCCUCCUUAUUUUUAGGAAGCAGAAAAUAGCCUAUUGUGUUAUAAUUAGCCACCGGUGCCCACCCAAAUAUGAUUACUAUGGCAAGAACUUUUGCUUCUUUUUGUGUGUGUGUGUGUGUGUGAGACGGAGUCUCGCUCUGUUGCCCAGGCUGGAGUGCAGUGUUGCAAUCUCAGCUCACUGCAACCUCUGCCUCCUGGGUUCAAGCAAUUCUCCUGCCUCAGCCUCCCAAGUAGCUGCGAUUAUAGGUGUGCACCACCACGCCUGGCUAAUUUUUUGUAUUUUUAGUAGAAACGGGGUUUCACUGUGUUAGCCAGGAUGGUCUCGAACUCCUGACCUUGUGAUCCGCCUGCCUUGGCCUCCCAAAGUGCUGGGAUUACAGGUAUAAGCCACCGCACCUGGCCAGAUCUUGAUCAUUUUUAAAUGUCCUGAAAUACUUGGGAAAUCUUGAAAGAUUCAUAUUUCUUCAAGAUCUCUAAGCAGUUUUUAAAAAAAUCCCUACAAGCUCAGUUAAAACUAAAUGUUCUAAACAGUGAGAAGUAUAAAUUUUCUUUCACCUGUCUUCUAAUUAGAGCCUCUUACUCAUCUGUAGCACGAGUCAUUUAUUUUGUCUAGUACAAAGAAUAUUUCGAAUACUCAUGACUAAAGAGCUCAGGAGUUCUAGCUAAAGAAGAAUCUUGAAGCAUUGGAGUUUUGAAAAUCUGCAUAAAGAUUUUGAAGAUUUUUUAAAGAUUCAUAUUAUAACAGUAUACCGUUGGUCUAAUUUUUCUUAAUCUACUAAAAACGAAAUAGCACAGGUCAGAUGUGACUUGCUUGCUUUCUGCUCCUGUACAAUCCAGGAGUGUUAAUCAAAAAGCAAAAUUUGUGACAUCAGUUUUAUUUCCAUGGCUACUGAUUGUAAUAUUACAAACAUGAGAUUACUGGCUAGUUCAUCAUGAAGGUUAAAGAAGAUUCCUCCUUGGAUAGGAUCUCCAAAACCAACACCAAGGGGAAUAUUAUCAGAGCUGCUUCCAGCAGCGUGUCCUUUCAAAAAUGUUCUCAUUAUUCUGAGAGCUUUGUUUUAUUUUGUGAGGGUUUUUAUCAUUUGUUGUUGGUGGUUAAUAUUUUAAUUUUAUGUGCUUGUUUGUUUUAUUUAUUCCUCCACCCCAGGUGACCGUGUAGGAAAAUGGUUAUUUUAGAUGUUAGAAGCCCCUCUGUUAAGAAGCAGUUUCUGCCUUCGUUUAAUUCUUCUUCCACAAAUAAGAUUUAUUUUGGAACUUCAGUCAAAAACAUCUGUACUUUGUACAGGACAAACAUCUGCCUUCCUACAAGAGCUGCUGGCCUUCCUGAUGUUAGAUAAAUGCAUUUUGUUCUUUGAAAGCCCCUCAUAGAGAAGAGACUGUACAAUAAGAGAAGCCCACUCAUUCUUGAAUCCAGAGCGCCUCGUUGUGGCUCAAACAUGUUACUACAGAAGACCGUUUAUCAAUUUGCUAUUUCUCUUCUCCCCAAACUUAAUCAGUUUUAAAGGUAGAAUAUAUUUUAAUAAAUAUAUUAUUUGACCAUGCCAUAUGGUCAAAGCUUCCAGGAACACAUAGAUAUGUGUUACCAACUUGGAAGAUAAACUGGGGUUGGGUACACUCAAGUUAUUUUUCUAAUAGUGAUGGAAGACGUGUGCUGAUAAGUUUUCAAAGUCUUAUCUGAACCGCCUGAUGACUGACAACGUGCGUUUGAGAGAUUUUGCUUCUCCUGGGAAGCUUGCCCUGAUUCUCCUGCUGCUUCUUCCAAAGGUUCGUUUUGUUUUUUGGGUUUUGUUUUUGUUUUUUUGCAUAUUUUCCUGUACUCCUUACUAAAAAUUCUUCAGGGCAGAGCUGCUGUCUUACCUUUGUAUUCUCAAUGCACAGCACAGUGCCUGGCAAAUAGCAGGUCCCCAGUAACACUAGAUGAAUGACAGGUGUUUUAGGACCAACUGUGGUGGAUCAGAAGAAUAAAAUCCAUAAUCCUGGCCUGUGUCCUGACCAUCCAAGUAUAUGGUUAGUCUUUAUUACUGUGUUUUUUUGUAUUUACUCUGUUAAAAUUACCUUAAAUAUAGUGAGCUUUGCUUAAUGAGAAACUGAUGUAGCAAAUAGCAGACCCUGUAAUACAGCUGGUCAUUUUAACACAGUGCCUUUUCUCCUCCUGACUCACUGACUUUUGGUUUGUUUUGCUAAAUCAUUACCUUGUAAUGUCUAGUUUUUAUUCAAAACAACUGCUACUAAGUACUACACCAGUAAAACGUUCUAGUGGAUAUUAUAAAUUCAAAAAUAUUUCUAUGUACCCUUAUAACAGGGAAUGCUGAGUUAAUGCGUUUUUCACAAAAUAGAGAUUCUCUAACCAUUUUUUGGUUGUCCCCUUACCGUCUGUACCAAAGCAAGCUAUGUAGGACACUGUUUUUUUCAAAAGGUGCAUUUAAGUAUGUUUUAAGAAUUGAGGUAUAUCCCACCAAGCUCGUGUAUUUAUUCAAGAAGCAUUUAUCUCCUGUUAUAUGCUUGGCAUUGUGCUGGAGUUCUGGAGGUGGCUAAGACAGUCCUUCCUGGAGCUCACGGGGGAGCCCAAGGAGCCCUAAUAUCAUGUGAUCUGUGCUAUAACAAGGACUAUAAACACAGAGGGCUGAGGCAGCACUUGGAGAGGGUUGUGCCUAUGAGGUUCUUGAUAAAUGCUGAAUAAGCUGAAUUCAGGGCCUUCUCAAGGUGAGUGAAUCACCUUUGUGUAUUGCAAAGGAAAACUAAGAAUAGUGUCUUGGAUGACAGGGAAGAAUAACUGUACAAAUAAAUGUUACAUACCACACUUAAAAAUGUCAACUUGGACAAGGCAAGUAAGGAACACAUGGAUUUUAGGUGUGGCCAGUGAAAAUCAGAGACUCUGACUAUAAUCCCUUUCUAACCUCCCCUUCAGUGCGUAACUAACACUGUUUUCACAAAAACUCUGAAACUUUCUUUUCCAGGCUUUUAUACAAGUUGUUUCUUUUGCCUGGAACAAUCACUGCCACUCCAUCUCCAUACCAACUCCUUUCACCCUGGAGGAAGCCUCCUCUGUCUCAUAGCACUCUGCACUUCCACAUCAUAGCGCCUACCAUACCAUAAUGUAAACAGGUCCACCCAUUUACCUCCCUGCAUCCCCUGCACAUGGCAAAGGGUGUAUGUCUGUUUUUCUCCGGGACCCAACACAUGCUCAGCACCUCAGGCUUAAUAAAGAUGAGUUAACUCAAAUUAGUUAAUUUAAUUCCAAGUUGCUCUCUCAUAUAGCAUCUCUGUAUGGGACUUCAAAAUACCAGAUAUUUUUUAGUUGACCCUUUUUAUUUUAUACUGAAGCCUUUUCAUAAGAUGGGAGGACUAUAAAAUCCCUCCCCUGCACGGAAUCCAAGCAAUAAUACCUUUCCUUCAGUGGUAAACAUGUGAAGCUUCUUGGAAUUUAAAAAACUAUUUUUUAAUAAGGAGAUAUACAGUCUGGGAUCUGCCCUUGAGCCUGAUUUCUCAUCUAUAAAUGAGGAGAUGGGCCUAAUGAUCUCAGAGGACGUUCCAGCAAAAGUUAUUCUCAGAAGCCAUAUAAUAAAUGUUAUAAAACUACCUUAUUACUGCCAACAUUUCACAUAAUAUUAAGAUUUUGAAGAGUACUCAUGAGUAGUUUUGACAGAAAUUGUAGAGACUAUCUCCCCACCAACCUCUAGAACAUAACAGCUAAAUGAUUUUCGUUGACUAAUUGAAUGAAUGAGGAAAAAAAGCCACAUGGCAAAAUCCCAAGUAAUAAAAAAGGAAAUAUUCUCACAGUUGAAGGAAUUUUCAAGAAGGAAAGGGAGAAUUGUCUGCAAGGGUACAAGGUGACAUUUAUAGUGAAAGGAAUUAUUUAAGUUCUUCCAUUAUUUAUUUACACAGGAAAGGGCCCAUGAAUUUACAGUGAAAAACUCUUCUAAUAAGGGAAUUAAGGCUAUGAAACUAACAUAGCUGUAUUUACCAGUACUUGAUAAAUGUCAUCAGCUAAUGAUUUGAUGAGAUAUCUUUGUAACAUUUAGUCACAAGGAGUCCUGGGAAAGUACUGUAGGUGUAAAGGAAGAAUGGCCUAUUCUAAGCAGAUUUUGUUUCCUUGUCUCUAUUAGAUGGCUGUUUUUCUGGAGCUUCUAACAGUUUUCAAACACAGAGUGCAAAUGUGUUUGUUGUCAGUGAGGCCGCCAUUUGGAGUUGGUGCAGGAGCUCUGCAGCUCCUUUUCUAUGUAACAGUGGAAGUGUGGUGGAGUUCAGUCUAGCUAGGGCCCCUUCCUGUCAUAAAUAAGAUUACUUUCAUUUCACUUGUGGAGUGUGCUAUUCCUCAGAGUAAUGAAUUUCCUCUGUGCCUUUGAGCAUAUAAACAUGGUUUUCAUUAGCUUUCUCUCUCUUAAAAAAAAACACACACACACACACACACACAGAAAGGAGGGGAGAGGGAGAGGGAGGUAAAAGAAAGAAUCUGAGCAAAAUUAAUAAGAUGUCAAUUAACUCCAUAAAUGCAGAUGCCUUUUUUGCCGACUGGCUAGAACAUGCUGAUGAGCAGUACCAGAAAAGCACUGGUUCAUCUCUCCUGAAAUGCUAAGAAAAUGAAAUGGGGUAGAGAAAGGUAAAAAUUUUAUCCUACAUGAACAAAGGAAUGAAAGAAAAAUAAAGAGAGAAAAGAAUAUUCUUUUUUGAAUCUUGCUGUUAGGAGAACUAUUUCAAACAGGCCAUGAGAGUGGCCCCUCGGACCAAAUAGCCAGCCCUGGGUUCUUCUGGAAUUAUGGGCACUUCACAGAGGACCAACCUAUUUGACCAGGAUCACAGUGCAGCCUCUGCCUCCACUUCCCUGCCUUUUGUGUGUGUGUGUGUGUGUGUGAGAGAGAGAGAGAGAGAGAGAAAGAGAGAGAGAGAUUUUAUGCUAAUAAGGUAUCCCAGCCUUUCCCUAUUUCAAAUUUACCCCUCUGUGACUUGUAAGCCAUGCAAUUCGUAGGGCUAAAUAUGCAGUUGUUCGAUUUCACGGUUUGGAAUCUCUUGUCAAGGGGUGAGUCAUUAUAACACGGCUGGGCUUUUCUCAUUGUUGAUGGUGCAUACUUGAACCUGAAAACUAUUUAGGAUCCAUUGACCCUUUGACUUCUGCCAGGAUCUUUCUUGCUGUUGUUUUUGGAAAUUUGUGGGGCAGGGAGUAGGGGGAUGGAGUCCUCUCAAAUUAACCCAUAGAAGGAGUUAAGCUAUUAAAAAAAAAAAAAAAAAAGCCUAAAACCUGGUUUUUCAAAAUUACUUAUUCUCAAUGAAAAAUCCCCAGAUUUGUGUUCCCAGAACCUUUUCCUCUCCCCACAAUCAAUGUCGGUUUCAGCCUCCAAUUCAUAGUAUAUUAUGUACUUGUUUAUCCUCUAGAGAGGAAGAAAUAAUAAUGUUAUGAAGGCAUCAAGGAAUUAAAUUCCAGGCCACAGGUUGUCACUGACAAUUCACUGCAGACCAAACUUGUAACCCAGAUAAAGAAGCUUGAAGCGUUUCACAGUGAGGUGUCUUCCAGCUUUGACCUCCUGGAUAGGUGUUCUUGUUACAGUUUAGAAGUGCAGCUGGUUUCUAUUUGAAAUGAGAAGAAUGGAGUUAUUUAAGGAGCCAGUGCCUCUCAUAGGUGAAAUCGGCUUUGCUGAAAUGUACACAACACACUACAAGGAACCUUAAAAACAAACUUCCAUUUCACUUAGCUGCAGCACAGGAAAUUGUUUCUGGCUUGUUUUUGUUGUGAACAGAGAGAACACUGCAUAUUAGAAAUUCCCUGUAGUUGUUUAAUAUUUGCUCAGUAGUGUCCUGGUUCCUAAUCAAGUCCUUCUUCUCACUAAAUCCUGUCAACUCUGUCACUGUUUUGAUUGGAAGCAUGAAUUGUAACACUGAAAAAUCUCUCAGGACAGUAAACCUCUGCAGCUGUGGAAGGCUGGAGCUAUUUACUGGUAUUAUUAAAGGAACCUGAAUGACUUCUUUGGGGGGGAAAAAAAAGCAAAGAUGCAGUGAAAUUCAUAAGGUGCACAGAGAUUUAGGAUGAAGGUUUUAUUAUGAGCACAGCCUCAUAAUACUAUCCUCAUAGAAAGAAUACAGAAUAGUAACAAUUGUUUCAUGAGUUGGCAAACAUAAUAUUCUGAUGUCUGCCUUUUUUAGGGGGAAAAUAAAGUCCAAAUGUAAAAUAUGAAAUCAGACAUAGCUAGUGCUUUGGAACAGUGUUUGAACUGGAUGCUUUUUCAAGGUACGCUAUAGAAACAAAUGUCACCUUUAUUUCCUGAAGGCAUUUUGAAGAGUUUGCCGUUGGUCUUUUAAGGCAUGAAUUUUCUGGAACAAAAGAGGUGCAGAAAUUUUAAAUUGUCACCAUUCUAAGGACAUAACUGAUUACACUACCUGCUGCUAUGUAUUUGGGAUCUGAGGAACGUCCUGAGAGUGUAAAGACAUAUGUUGGAGAGGCUGGACCGCGCCCCCCAGCCCGGCCCCAAAAUGGGAAAAGAAGCAAAAGGAAUGAAAACUUUCACUUGAGAGAGGUGACCAAUACCAUACCUAAGAUGUUUCUCUUCCAAAAUGUUUCUUUGUUCACUUAUUCAUCCUUUAUUCAAUGAUUUAUUCGUUUCAGAAAAGUUUAUUGAGUAUCUACUGUGAGCCCAGAACUGUGCCAGGUACUGGGAGGUCUAGUUUAAAGGCAGCUUGCCCACAAGGACAGGGAUUUCCGCCAAGAAUGUUCUGUCCUCAUUGCUAUAGUGUAAGAAGCAGCUGGAUUCCCAAGUCAGCCUUGACAUUCAGCAGAACUUAGCGUGUCUGCCUCUAAAAGCACAAACCUGUUUGCUAGACUGUUCUUGUCAUUGCCAAUGUAUUUACUAUUGUGUAAAAGUCACGUUUUGAAUAUAAAUUUUUGUCGUAUCUUGAAGAAGCAGUACAAAGCCCUAAGAAACAGUUCAUAGAAAAUAGUUUUAAGUAAUUCGAAGAAAGUACCUGUAAAUGUAGAGUAAUUGCGAAGCUGUCAGGAAUAAACAAGAUCUUGUAAAGCUAUAGAAAUGUGUUGAAUAUGUUUUCUUUGAGGCCAGAGCAAGAUAAUAACUCGGGAAGAAACUUCUAAAAUAUCAACUCAGCAAAACAAAUGCAAGACUUUUGAGGACUCAGUUAUCAUGUGGGAGGCUGGAUGCUGUGGAGGAUAUGAGGUAGAAUAAGAUGGUCUCUAAUCUAAUCUCAGAGAGGAAAUGAAACAAGCCCUUGACUUAGAAGGUGAUGUGCUCCAAGCUCUCAGUGCAGCCCGAGAAAGUAUAGUGAGCACAGAGCUCCGGUAGGCCAGCAGGCCAGUGAAAUGCAAGGGGUUUUGGGAAAGCUACAGGAAACCAGACUGAAGGUGUUUACAGGGCCAUCCAUGUUCCCACCUGGAAUGUGUGUGCUGCUUCCAAACUUGUUCCUCCAGAAAGAUAGCUUCAAAUUGGACAGGGUUCUGAGAAAUGCAAUUAAAAUGAUAAAGGGAAGCAGGGGGUGAUAGUGGGAGAGCUCAGAUGCCAUAAUAGUGAAAAAACAAGAAGGUUAGGAUCCUUCAGUCUGUAGAAAUGGAGGUUGAGACUAUGUGUGUCUAUAAAUGGAGGUUAUAUAUAAGGUCAGCACUAAGUCUCAGAAUUACGAGAACGAAGGGAAAGCCAUAAUCAUUUGUGAAGACUUUGACUCCAGUUUCUUCUUUUGUAAUCCAGAUUCCAGAAUAUGUUCAGCGGCACAUCUGUCCUACAAGGUGCUUGCUAAAAAAAGGUAUUCUUUAGCCAAGUAAGUUUGAAAAUCUCUGCAUACCAUGUGUUCUUCCAGUAGAUUCUCCCUUUACAUUUGAUAUUAAAAGAUCUCAAAAGGUUGUUCUUAAGGAAAACUUAUUUAACUUUGUGGUUCUCAACCAGUAUUUACCAAACUCAUUUGACCAUGUAAUCCUUUGUUUAUUUAGUGCCUAUGAGGACUUUGGAAAAUGCUUCUGGGAAGAUAGGACUCUAAGAUUAUUAAGGUCCCUGGAAGGAAGUUAAUCCAUGACAGAGGAAGCGCUACCAACACUGUGAAAUUUAUUACUUCUAGAGCCAAUCAAUACUGGACGAAAAUAAUAAAGGGGCUGAUAGUGAGAGAGGACUAAUAGUUUGCAAGUAGUAGGAAUUUACAGUCAUUUAUGGAAGAUGGCAAGUUCGUCAAAGGUAGUUGGGAGGUGUGGCUGACCAUCCAAAGGAAAGCCAUUAGAGUCCCCACAGUGCUUUUAGAGGGGUUGUUAAGACCCAGAUCUCCACAUCAGGCUUUAGAUUGUUCUGUCAGGAUCACACAUCUCUUCUGCACCAUCAAAAGAGAAAAGUACAUAGAAGAAACUCAUUUAAGUUUUGGCUGAAUCAAGCAGAUCGUUCUGCAUGAUAGUGAGAUUAUAGACAAUUGGAAAGUACUUCUAUUGAACUUUGAGGCCAGUCACAUUCUAUUAAGUUUCAGUUCAUGCCCAUUAAAAUAAUAGCAGCUGGAUUCUAUAGCUUUUCUCUGAAAACCUGGCUAAGCAUUCAAGUUCAACAGUUUUGUAGAUUUGUGCUUUUUUUUCUCUAGAAAGCUUUCAUUAUUUUGAAGAGCGUUUUAUACAUGCACCUCUCCAUUCCCUGACCCUGGCUGACUUUUUACCCUUUCUCUUCCCCACCUCACUGAGCAAGUUUACAUAGCUACAGUGUCCUUCCAACAUUGUAAAGAGUUUUGUUGUUGUUGUUAUUUAUUGGACGUUAGGGAGAGCAAAUGAAUAUGAUAAGUUUAAAAACUAAGUCUUAGAAUAGUUUUCUUUCUCUCAAGCACAUUUUAGUUUCUUCUCCUUUUGCUUCAUCUUUCCCAUUGUGCUCAUUAUUCUGCCUUCUCCAUGCUUCUCCAUGAUGCUCUGUGCCAGGGUGGGGAGGGAGAGGGGAAGGGGGGGUGUCAUUCUACAUGGACUGCACCAGUAGGCUCUCUUGCCCUAUGGUUUCUGGAUGGGAUUGGCUAAUGCAGAGGCAUCAGCUGUAGGUUUUAAGAGGAGAAUGAGGCCACCCUCUCCAUGGAGCUGUUUUCUCUGUAUUCUAGUGCUUCCUGCAUGGGCUCCUUGGGCCUACGCAUGACCCUGGACUACUAGCCCUCCACUCGUUAGUUUCCUUUAACCUUGCCCACAUGUUUGUACAUAGUCCUUUUAUUCAACUCUCCUCAAAUUACCUAGUUUGAGUGAGUUAUCUGUUUCCUGCAGAGACUUUGACUGAUGUACCCACCUUCCUGUAACCCUCUCCUUUUUGCUCUCCAGCCAGGAACAUCAUUCAUUAGAGCCCAGCUCAUGUUCAUCUUCUUAAGGAAGCCUCUCUGUUCAGCAUGAAGCUCUUCUUGAGAUCUCCUAGCUCUUACAGUCUGCCACACUCAUAAGCACCUAAAAAUGCUCUCUCAUGUACUGACUUAAAUGCACUAAGACCAAUGCUCCUCAUGCUUAUAAAUAAUGUUUCAUGGAUAUGUAGGAAGGAUGGCUAGUGAGUAGAGGUUGCCAAUUGGCAGCCUGACUUUAGGCAGACAAUUAGCAGUUAUCAAACUUUGAUAGAGUACUUCCAGGUGCUGUUAAGCCACACUUAGAGUUGGAUACUAUUAUUACCUCCAUUUUACAGGUACAGAUGCUGACACAUAGAGAAGUGAGGUAGAUUGCCCCAGAACAUACCUAUAAUAAGUGCUUGAGCUAGGAUUUGAACCUAGACAGUCUAGCUCCAGAAUCCAUGCUCUUAACUCUGUACUAAGCUACCUCUCACAGUGCUUUUAAAUUUUCAAAGCAACAAUUAUCAGUAACAAGUCUAUCCUUCCUCCCUCCCUCCCUCCCUCCCUCCCUCCCUCCCUUCCUUCCUUCCUUCCUUCUUUCCUUCCUUUCCUUCUUUCUCUCUUUCUUUUCUCUCUCUCUCUCUCUCCCUCUCUCUCUCUCUCUCUCUCUCUCUCUCCCUCUCCCUCUCUCCCUCUCUCUCCUCUCAACAAGGUCUUACUCUGUUGCCAAGGCUGCAGUGCAGUGGCACAAUCAUGGCUCACUGUAACCUUAAACUCCCGGGCUCAAGCAAUCCUCCCCUCAGCCUUCUGAGUGGCUGGGACUACAGGCACGUACCACCAUGCCCAGCUGAUUUUUAAUUUUUUUUUAGAGACAGGGUCUCAUUACGUUGCCCAGGUUGGUCUCAAACUCCAGACCUCAGGCAGUCCUCCCACUUCGGCCUCCCAAAGUGCUAGGAUUAUAGGCGUGAGCCACCGUGCCCAGCCCAUAUUUCAUUUUAAAACCUGCAUUUCUAGUGUCUCUUGAAAAAAUGGAAGAUCUGGCUGUUGGGAUCCAUAGGCCACAGCAACAGUUGGCCAGAGCAAGCAGGAGCUGCCCUGUUCAGGUGGGGUCCAUGCCCUUCACUUGUGAGGGCCUCUACCCAGCCUGUUCCUGAAUCCAUGCUCCUUCCUGACUUCCAGAGGCCUUGAGUCUGGGAUCUCUGCAUGAAAAUGAGUUUUACAUGUGGUCUUUGGAAAUCACUUGCAUGCCUUUAGUCAUUUCCCACAUGAACUUCUGUUUCCCCAGCUAGAUUAGGUUUAGGGAGGACAGUCUAUAUUUUAAGCUUGCCUCAAAACCUAAAACAGAACAGGUUAUACUCAAUAAAAAACCUGUGAAUUUGAAGAAAACAACCUGCUUCAGUUAACUAAGUAAGCUAUUAAUAACUUAGGUAACUCAGCAAGGACAGGAGAGGCAUGUUUAUUCUUGGACUGGAGUUUAUCCCUUAAAGCAGUUUGCUUCUAAAGCCAAACAAGUAAAAUCUCUGGGUAUUCUUGAAGAUAGCUGCUAUUGGCAAUAUUGCCCCUAUUUUUGAUGAAAGGCGAAUAUCUACUUCACCUCCAGGCCCAAUGGUGUGAAGUUUGUAGGAGAGAAAACAACCACUGCUUCAGAGAGCUAUGGUAGAGGGGAGAGCCAAUUUUAGGUGGAGCAAGGUGAAAGGAAGUUUCAAAGAAGUUGAGAACAUAGAGGCUUUUGCUGGUGAUGGACAUGAGUCCAGAAGGCACAGUGAUUGGGGGCUGGGCAAGGGGAAAUGGAGGGAGAGCAGGAAUUUUCAGAGCCCAUCUUGGGAACAGGAGUGAUGAGGAAUGACUGGGUCCCUCUGGUGACAGAUGUACAAAGGGAUGCAUGACAUGCUUUUGAUGGUCCUGAUGGUUCCCAAAGCAGAUUGCAGUCAUGAGGCAGUGAGGGUUGAAGGAGCGUCAGGAGUCGGGGAGGGAGAGGUUUGGCCAGGAACACACACAGUGCUGGGUCCCCCUCCUUCCUCUUUUCUCCUGGAGUGUGGAGUGGAGUGCAUAACACUCAGUAGGGCUUAUUAAAGGGCAAGUUCUCCAGUUAGUACAAUGAAGUAUGUGGCAGAAAACCCUGUUGGUGAAUGUCGGCUUUACUUUUGUGAAUGCACACUCAAGGUAGAAGGUUUCAGUAGAAUCUAGAUGUUAUUCUAAAGCACAACUAUGAAGCAUGCUUCAGUCAGGAUAAGAGCAUAUAAUCCUUUUUUUAAAUGUAAUACUCUUUGUGUCUCUCUGAUUGAAUGUUUUAUUGUUCCAUCUUAUUAUAGCUUGACCCUUCUUUAAGGGGCCAAAGGACUUCAGGAAAUAGAUGCAAAUUUAAGAAAAUGAAUCAUCUUUCCCAAAACAGGAGUCUGUUUUAAUGGAAUAAUCAGCCUUACUUAUCGAUGAAGGAACAUGAAGAUCUUAUAGUGCUUACAGCUGUCUCUUUAAUUUAAUGUAUGAGGAGAGGGAAACCUCACAAACUUCUCCUUAUGAAAAAGUGGAAGUGGUUGAGGGUGCAGAAUUGGCCAGAACUUGGGGCUCUUGUUCUUUGCUGAGCAGGGUCAAAUGCCUGACCUCCGGGAGGCAAGCCAGGGGCUUUCCUAUCAGCAGAGAUCAGCAGUGGUGGGUUACUGCUGUUUACUCUCCUUGCAACUUUAUGGAAAAGUACAGAAUUAGCAGCUCUCUCCAACAUCUAUUACCUUGGUCUCAUGGACUUGGGGAGUGGAGUCAUGACCAAAGUUAAGAGUAGAAAUCCUGGCCGGGCACAGUGGCUCACACCUGUAAUCCCAACACUUUGAGGGGGCCAAAGACGAGUGGAUCACUUGAGGUCAGGAGUUCGAGACCAGCCUGGCUAACAUAGUGAAACCCCGUCUCUACUAAAAAUACAAAAAUUAUCCGGAUGUGGUGGCACAUGCCUGUAGUCCCAGCUACUGGGGAGGCUGAGGCAGGAGAAUUACUAAACCCAGGAGGCAGAGGUGGAAGUGAGCCAAGAUCACGCCACUGGUGUCACUUCAGCCUGAGCGACAGAGCGAGACUCUGUCUUAAAAUAAAGAAUAGAAAUUUCUGUCUGUCCUGAGAGCAGUGAGGUUUCAUGGGUGCUGGGGGAAUGGAUACUUUACCCCUAAAAAUACCCCCAACCAUAAGCAGUUUCCCUGACUGUCUUCCUUACUUCCAGUGGUGCACCAUCUGUCUUCAGGGUGUCAGGGUGGGGAUUCACCACAGGAAGUUUCUAGAAUGCCUCCGACCGUAUUUGCAAGUGUUGAACCCUCUCACCACCUAACCUCCAUUGGCCCAUCUGUCCCCAGCCACACUUGGCACAUAAUCAAUGCUUUCAAAUUCUAACUCUACCACUUACUACUUAGCUGUGUGACCUUGGGCAAGCUACUUAACAUCUACGUGCCUUAGUUCCUUCCUCUGUCAAAAGGAAUCAUAAUAGUACCUAUCUUGUAGGGUCAUUGUAGGAAUUAAAUGUAGUAAAUGCCGGGCAUGUGUAAGGGCUAUCUGAAUGUUAGCUAUGGGACUUAUUCUGAUUACAAUGGCAGUGGGUGUCUGGCCAGCCACCAGAUCACCUUUAUGCAAGAUAAUUACCUUUCUAUUUCUCUGGUAAGCAGACAUGGGUAAUUGAAGUUGACCUACCAUGUCCUCCGUGUGGCCCACAUUUACGUUCCUUUCCAUGCUCUCCAAUCUUCUGGUUUUCCUGUAGCUGAGAUACCCACUGGAUUGGGCAGCUCUAGACUACAGCUAUUCUGAAUCAGGCCUCAGAGGUCUCCAUCACUGACCACAUAUCGUGUGCAUGUUCUUAUUCAGUUUCCUUUUGUGGCUAAGGAAUGGACACCUAAGUACUGCUUCUUUUUAUAGAAGGCUCUGACUAGCAUAUUUGCUGAUUAAAAGGAAGGCCUCACAGAGCAUUCAUUUUGAAGAGCAUAGUAAUACUUAAGAACCAGGACUAUUUCAGACAUUUAUUGCAAACUGUUUAUUUCCUAAAAUAAGGAGGGCAUGCUUUUUGUUUACAUCCUCCUAAUGAGAAUUCCUCAGGGGUUUGAAAACUGUUAUUGUGCCCUUUUCGUCUUCCCCUACAUUUCAGCCUACCCAUCCAAGAAGCAUCUGACCAGUGCUAUCAUGAAGGUUGUGAUUUAACUUUGAAAGGAAUCCUUUUCUACUGUCCUCCUUAGAGUUGUAGCAAGCUGCCUUCAUUGACCAAAUGUACAUCAUAACUUAUCAUAGUUCAAAUCCUAUCACCUGUUUCUGUCUCCUCUGGGAGAUAUUCCUUGACCCCAUCCCAUUAAGUUCUUCUCCCUCUGUGCAAUUUCUGUACAGGGACACAACUUUAUUGUUGUCCUUAUCACUCUACUCUAACAUUUAAUGACAGUUUAAUACUGCUUUCUAUGUGCCAGGCACAGUGGUAGAUUCUAAAAAUCUAACUGCAAAUAAAACUUGAAGACAGUGGUAUCUCGUAGAACAUUCUGUGAGGAUGGAAAUGUCCUAUAUCUGCAUUACCCAGUAUGAUAGCUGCUACCCAUAGAUGGCUAUUGAGCACUUGAAAUGUGGCUAGUGCAACAGAGGAACCAAAUGUGUAAUUUUAUUACUUCAUAUGUACAUGUAAAUAGCUACAUGUGGCUACUGAUUACUGUAUUGAACAGCACAGCUCUAAAACGUAAGUCUGAUGAGGACAGAGAUCCGUGUCUUUUGUUUAUCACUCUACUCCCAGGGCCAAGAACAGUGCCUGCCAUAUGGCAUGAAUGAAAGAAAGAAAAGAAGGACGAAAGGAAGGGAGAGAGGGAAAAGAGAGAGAUGGGUGAUCUGGUUUGGAUCUGUGUCCCCACCCAAACCUCAUGUUGAAUUGUAAUCCCGUGUUGGUGGUGGGGCCCAAUGGGAGGGGACUGGAUCAUGGGGGCAGAGUUCUUGUGAAUGGGUUAGCACCAUCCCCUCAGUGCUGUUCUGCUGAUAGUGAGCGAGUGAAUUGUCAUGAGAUCUGGUUAUUUAAAAGUGUGUAGCACCUCCCACCUCUCUCUCUUCUUCCUACUCCCACCAUGUAAGAUAUCUGCUCCCGUUUUGCCUUCCGCCAUGAGUAAAAGCUCCCUGAGGUCUCCCUAGAAGCAGAUUCCACCAUGCUUCCUGUACAGCCUGUGGAACCAUGAGCCAAUUAAACCUCUUUUCCUUAUAAAUUGUCCAGGCUCAGAUAUUCCUUUAUAGCAGUGUGAGAACAGACUGGUACAACAGGUCUCUGACCUUGUAGAGCUUAAAUGUAGUAGAGACCCAUUUGUUUAUAUAUUUGCUUAUAGAUCUUUAAGUUCCAGAAGACAGGGAUUGUCUUUUCUUUGCCCAUAUCCUUAUACCCAUUGCCUAAAACUGUAUCAAGGCUCAUAGGAGGGGCUCAAGAAAUGUUAGUUGAGUUGAAACCAAUGCUGAAUAAAUGCAAGAUUGGUAGUGGUGGGGAUAGUAAUCCUAGUAGUGGUUGUUGUUAAUAGGAAGAAAACUUACCCUUCCCCAGUGAUAUUAAGCAAGGCUGCUGUUGUUCAUAGUAGGAAGAAAGAUACCCCACCCAGUGCUGUAUAUCAGACAAGCAAUGUUGGUGCCGUCUGGUGGUGGUAUCCUCUCCAGGCCUUCUAAGUCUAUCAAGCAAAUCUGCCUUCUCUGACAUAUCCUCACCUCUUGCUCCCUGUUUGGCUUGGAAAUCCAGCUACUUACCACUAAAAUCCUUUAUAAAGAGAAAGGGAGAUAGUCAUGAUUAUUUAUUAUGCCACCUUUAAGCCCUGUCCCCAUCAUCCCCUUAUUCGUGUGUUUCUCACAAGGGGCCUCUCUUGGUGCCUUUCUCUGCUCUGAUGCUUCCUUUUUGAACCGUAUCAUUCUGACCUUCCUCUUCCCUUCUCCUUGACAACCAUGACCAAGCUGUCAGAUUAUUACAGGACAUCCAAUAAUUAUUGAAUAGUUAUUUAUUAUUCAGUAAACCACAAGAUCACUUAAUAGCAAAUAGUGGAAAAAAUGUUGGCUUUGUACGUGGACACCUUGGAUUCAAGUCUUAGCUUUACAGCUUACUACUUAGAUUAAUUUGGGCCAAUUAUGUAAACUCUCAAACCCUCAGUGUCCUCAUCUGUAAAAUGGCAUAAUAAUGCAUCUCUUAUAAAUUUACUCUGAGGAUUAAGUGAGACAUUGUAGGUAAAGUAUCUAGCACAAUGCUUGGUGUGCAAUAAAUGUAAGCUUUCUUCUCUCCUUAAAUAUACCAACAUAUACAUAUUCCCAAACAUAUACAUAGGAAUUUAACGUCAAUUUUGAGUGUUCAAGUUUUAAUCACACUUCACCGUUUUGUAUUGUCCUAUACACCUAUUUCACUGUUAAAAGAUUAAACUACUAAAAUAAUAAUCUUACUAUCUACCUUUCAUGUGGAAAACUAGUUUGUUUUAGUUUAUUAAUAAAGCUAAGCAUUGUCGCCAUGCAACAUAGUUGGAAAUUCCUUUUACAAGUAAUAAAAAGCCAUGUUUUUGUAUUUUUUAAAUUACAAAUCAAGCAAACCACCUAAUCAAGCCAAAUAAACAAAGAGAAACAAAAUACUGGAAAAACAGUUCGGUAAAAGGCAAAUCAGUAACGCUAAAAGGGAAGUACUGUACCUCCAAUGUAAAUUCUUCAGUGUAAUUAGGGUUAAUUCCCGUGCUGCUGUGUGCUCUCCUGACUGUCCUGGUAGAAAGAACAACAAUUUACAAACGUAAAUUCUCACUGUAGAACCUCCCUUUGUGGGAGACAUCUUCAGUUCUCUGGAGCCACUGUAUGCUCCCUCCCCAAAGACAACAUGAGCACUAAACAGCCCUUCAGCAAACUUAGUUCUAAGGAGGUAGCUGCACUGUGCUACAUAACUGCAGUUAGCUUUGAUUACUGUAUUGCAAAGUUAUAUUUGAGAAGUAUCAAAAUUGCUAGUGUUGUUUUACAAAGAAAGCAGCCAGUGUCAUAGUGUUUACUCUAAUCUAAUUCAUUGUUCUUGAUUAAUGACUUCUAUGCUAGAAGAAUGCUAGAUCCUUCUAGAGCAGGGGUCCCCAAACCCCCGGGUCAUGGACUGGUAUAGGCCUGUGGCCUCUUAGGAACCAGGCCGUAUACCAGGAAGUGAGUGGUAGGCAAAGACCCUUUUUCACCGCCUGAGCUCUGCCUCCUGUCAAUCAACAAGCACAUGUUGAGUUGUUGCUAUGUUAGUGUAACAGGUCCUCAACAACAAGUGCCCUUCCCAUGAGGGACUCUUGCUUCUCUCUGCUGGUACAAAUCUACCAAACCUGUUCAAAGGAUACCCACAGCGAGGACCAGGGGCAGUAGGCUGGCCUGGAAGAUAGGCCAAGACUCUGGGUAACGUGAUGCUUGGCGCUAUGGCCUGGGAACUUUGGAACUCAGGACUCAGCUUAUGGAUCCCCUGGCUCCUCUGUACACAAUCUGGCUGGAUUUCUUACCUUUCCUCCAGUAGAAUAGGUGCAAAGUCAGAUGCCUCAUGGAGCCACACAGAUAGUAUAAACAUGAAUGGUGGGUGGUUGGAGACUGUGUCCCAUCUAAAGGGAGCAGCUCCAGCCACUUGUUGCUGAGUUGGAAUGUGGGCCGAAUUUUGUAGUAUCUAGUUUUUCUAGAGAAGCUGAAAGUCUCUAUUUGUAUGUGAAAUCUUUUGAUUUUUAGAUAUAGAGAGCAAAAUCUGUUUGGGGCCUCCAACAGAAUUCAGGUGUCUACCAUCACCUGGCCACCUAAUGGGCGUUCCAGGUACGAGGCUUUUCUGGCCUUUCUCAACCUGUGCUCUCCUCAGACUGGAUACCAAAGGGAGCAAAGGCAGUACCCUGUGAAAGCACUUGAGUUUGCAGUCCCUGCCUCCCGCAACAUCCCAUUAUCCAGUCCCACCAUUUAGUGAGCAUCUGCUAUGCCCCAGGCACUGUGCCUGAGGGCUUGCUGGACAGGAGUGCAAAGAUUAAGAAAAUACAGUCCCUGAGGAGCUCCCUGGCUUGUGUGGAACACACAGGUAAAUAAAUAGACCACAGGAGAAAUGCCAACCAGAGGAGGCUGCCCAGUGUCCCAGCAGCUCAGCGACUGCCAUCCUUCCCAUUGCACAGAACAGCCCAGGAGGAUCAGAGAGGACAACAAGGAAGUCGUCUCUGACACCUCUUUAGACUCUCACAGUGGCCUGACCUUGAACCGUGAUGAUCAUAAUGCAACAGAUGGUGUUCUCUUUUGGUGAUUUCAAAGAAGUCGUGGUUUACCCAAAAACAACAUUAUAGAAGAAGCAGGCAAAAAGUGUAAAGCUCAUAGUCAAAUGGACGAGAAUGUCAAACAGUAUUUAAUAGGGGUUGGCAGGGGAAACAUGACCCUUCGCACAUUUUACCUUGAUGUCCCUGCCCUCCACACAUACCAGGUCCUGUCAGACACACAGUCAGCUGAGUUGAAUGUGAAAUAUCGUAGUCCAAUUUGUUUUUACAAAUUUUUCAUCAAGGCAAAAACCAAAACAAAGAAAAAUAAAUGCCCCUCUCAUGUUGAUACCUCCCACAGUUCCCUCUGAUUUGUGUCACCUCCUUCCUGCCCCCAACCAUUUUCGUAACACACUACCUCUGGGCAAGAGGAACAGAAUUGCAAUCUGAUGAGAGUUAUUAAAUGGAAUACAAAUGAAUUCAUUCACAGUCUACUAAUUUUGAGUAGAUUCAUGGUCAUUCACACUGGUAUUGGACUGAAGUCUCUUUUGUCCUGUGAAAUUAGGGAGUCAAAGCAAUUGAUUGGUGUAAAGAAGGUUUUAGGGUAUAGGCAAUCAGGGUGCUAAUUAUAUGUAGUCCUUGUCAAUCUGUUAAAGCAGGUGCCCAGGGAUUUUACUCGCCAACACUCUUGAAGGCUCAUCUUAUGUUCUUGAAAGUAAUAAUCAUUCAAUUCUUUAAAAGUCAACUCCAUGUAUUAACCCUUAUUGCUAAUUCAAAAUGCCCUGAAAUUAAAUUUCAGAGGAAAUAGUAGGAAGCAUACAUUUGGCUGGAUUUACAGAAAAGGAUAAGGUGGAUUUUGCCCCAGAUGAGGGUUUAUUUUCAUGGAACUUUGUUCUCCAACCCUAUAGCUCAGGGACUGUUGGAAUGGAUCAUAACACCCCAAAAUGUGUUUUAGUCUAAACAGUGUGUUAAUGGCAUACCAUGUCAUUAUUGUUAAUAUUAUUAUUAUUAUUGAUUAUUACUCAAAAGUAUUUCCUUUAGUAUUUUGAAGCAUCACUCUUGUUUUUCAUUUUUGCAGAGUCAGGAGUAAAUGCGCAGUCCAUUUGUGACUCUGUCGUUCUUGCCAGCUGUGGUUGAGCAUCAGUCUUCUUUUUGGGUGAUCUUACCAGGAAGGAGUUCCUCCUGACUACAAAGAAGUGUGGCUCCACACCUACAGUUGUUUCUCCAGCUGGGGCUAAAGGGGCUGGCACUAGCAAAGUUGAGAUAGUUCUUUUGAAAUUAACUUUCCCUUUCAUUUUCAUGAAUGUGGAAAUAAUACAUUCAUAUAUAUGAACAAGAAGGAUUUAAUCUCUUAUCAUUGACAUACUCUGACGGCUGAAUAUGCAGUUGGCCAUGGUACCUAAAAGUUUCUCAGGAUGCAAAGCACUCAUUCUUCUUUGAAGUAAAACCAGCCUUGCUUCCAUUUCUUGUUGUUUGGUACUUACAGUAUUUUCUAUCUCCUGCGAGGUCAGUGGCUAUGUCUGUCUGACCUCACACUUCAGCCUUGCAGUGCCUGGCACAUAGUAGGACUUUACUGAGUAUCUGAUGGAUGAUUGCUAAGAUUUUACCCCUUCAGUGUUACAUGUUUUUUUCAUUAUCCCAGGCCUUGCCAAUGACUGCAGCUUUCCUUGUGCACUCAUCUCAGUUUCACCACUAACUAGCAGGGUGACCUAGCCUAGAGAAAUAAUCUCUCUGGAUCCUAACUUAACCAUCUGUAAAAUGAAGGGGUUGGGUUUCAUCCACUCAAAAGUCCCUUGCAUUUAUACCAAUAUUCUACCAGGUAUUUGAAAGAAUUAGAUCAUCUAAUGAGGAAGAAUAUAAGGAAAAUAAUGUUACUACUCUUGAUUAGUAGUCAGAACAAGCUAGACUAUCUUAACUUUUAAUUGUGUGUCUCUUGAGAAGAUAUUUUUAGCACCAUGCCAAAUCCCAGAGUCCAAGGGCUGCCAGGGAUAUAGGCAUAGAAGACCCUCUGGGCAAAGACAGACUCCUCAUCAAAUAGUUGGGGUUUGGCCCUAAUUCCUUAUCUGACUGUCUAGGUUGGUGAGGGGGUUACACCAUAUAGAAGCCUCUGGGUCUGUUUUUGCCUAAAGUCUAUUUUCUCUGAGGUGAAGGAACCUGUUUUCCCCAGGCCUAAGCCCUGAGGUUGGCCUUUUUGAUGCUUUACCAUUCCCCAGGCCAGCAAUAAAAUGAAAAAGCAAUCUUAGAAAGCCUUUCUCUGAACACUAGACCACACCUAAUGGCCUUAUCCACUCCAGAGCUCCCAUCCCCUGGUUCUACUCCAAAGUGGGCCCCCCACAAGUAGGAGGCUUGUCUUUCUGCACGUGCUCCUGGGAAGGAUGAGAAGACACACUACAAUAGGCUUUUUCGCCUUUCUAUUCCUGCCACGGAAAGUUCCAGUUGCCCCUAACACCAGGGCCCUCCUGUGUUUUCCUGAGAGCUCUUUGAUCCCUUGAUCCAAGUGCAGAGGGCCUUUCUUUUGGGGCUUGAGUGGGAGGAGGGAAACCUCAAGCUCCCUUCAAAAGCUACACAUGGAGCCAACAAUAACAACUCAUUGGACAUAGCAGGAGCCUAAGGGAAAAGUUCUGAAGUGGGCGCAGAGGGGUUCAGUCCUAAAGAUUUCCAGGACUGUGGCAUGGAGAGGUACCCUCAGUCUGGGGGAAUAAGGUCAUGGUUACCUGAGCCAAACCUAGUCAAUAGCUGGCCUGGAGUCAUGCAUGCCCCUGAAGCAAGAUAAGGGUUAAACGUUUGGAAUGUGCCUGAUGGCACUGCUGUUCUGAGUAUUCUAUUUUGUUUUUUAUUCUGAGUAUUUUAGAUGCACACAUGCAACCAAGUGCUCAUUCUGAGUUUUGAAAGAAGACUUGAUUUUGCUUCCAGUGAGUGGUGUUUCCAAUAGAAGCACUGGAAUGCAGCCUUAUCUUUUCCUUCUCUUGGGUUGAUCCUUUGUCCUGGCUGCUGACCUUGCUCCUUCCUCACACAAGGAGAUUUUCUUGGUUGGGAAAAGUAACAGAUGCAGACAGCCUAAUUUGUUCUUGGCAAGAGCCACAAUCUGCAUUGCUGUGAGGGUCAGGAGAAUCAUAAAUCAUUCACAGAGUUCUGGUUUUCUGAGAUGAGAUGGGCCAGAUUAGUUAGAAUUUCAUUUUGUUCUCCCUCUUCUCACCCCAAGCCGCAUAUACUCCUAUAGCUGCUUAUCCACAACACCAGCAUCUUCCUUUUUAUUUCUCAGAAGGGGAAGGGAGGGAAUGUUCUCUCCAAAUGAACAUGAAACACAUUGAGUUGGUAUGUGAUGAUGCCAUGACGCAGUGACUGGGACAACUUGAAAGCUGAAACAUAAAACAGCUUUUAAAAAGGGAAAAUAACACCAAUGUGUUUCCAAUGUGCCCUGCACAGGAAACAGGGCUGGAGGCUCCAGUGACGGUCAGGCGACUCCACUCCAGCUGGAGGAUUUUUAUCAUUGCUCUGUUAUCGUCUGCACAUUACAGUCGCCAAGACCUCCUUGCUCAAGCUCUGGGAGGCAGUGGGGUCCUUAUGGCUAGAGAGACUUGGAAAGGCAUGACCUUGUGCAUCCCCCUGUCUCUUUCAGCAUGUAGGAUUUCAAGUAAGUCUGGUCCCUGACUGACUCAGGGGGUGUAAAUGUGUGAGGAAAAAACUUCCAUAAUCGAGGUGACUUUUUGUUUAGGCUUUAUUCUCUUUGAACUAGAGAUUGAGGAAGAAAGUGACUCAAAAGGCAGUACCAAGAUUUCAGUCAUUUGUUUAAUGUUGAAUAGGCAGAGAGUGACACUCUGGAUAGAUCUGGCAUUGACUGAGAGCCCUGUUUUACUGCCAUCAGCAGGACCAGUCUUCCUCUUUGCCACCACUGAGGAUCCACAAGCUAAUAUGGGACUCUUGUUCUUUACUGGAUUUUAGACCAGGAGGUAAUAGGGCACCCUCAGACCUCAUAUGUGGGACAUAACACAGCAGUGGAAUGCAUGUGGAAUACCACGAUGACCCACUUAUAACCACCGUGCUAUUUAGAAUUUUCAACCCCUCCCCCUCUCCUUUUCCUUCUGCCACUCUUUCUUUGCCCCUUUCCUUGUGAUGGUGUCAGGAAAGGUUUUAGUUCCUCAAAGUAGGCAUUACUUCCACAGCAGUCUUCAACAAAGGUUUAUUGUGAAAGACAUGAAAGGAGAUUGAAAGCUUUUGGAUUAUCCAUAAUCUUUAUUUCUCUUACCCAGACCAGGCAUGAUGCUACAUGCUGGUCAAACGGAAGUGACUCAGUUCUUGCUCUUAAGAAACUGAAUCUAGAAGAGAAGACACAAGUAAACACAAUAGUUGCUCUAGGGCAAGGGUCCCCAAUUCCUGGGCCACGGACUGACACUGGUCCACGGCCUGUUAGGAACCAGGCUGCACAGCAGGAGGUGAGCAGUGGGCAAGGGAGCAUUACCGCCUGAGCUCCACCUCCUGUCAGAUCAGCAGCAGCGUUAGAUUCUCUUGGGAGUGCGAACCCUAUUGUGAACUGCCUAUGGGAGGGAUCUAGGUUCCGCGCUCCUUGUGAGAAUCUAAUGCCUGAUGAUCUUUUACUGUCUCCCAUCACUCCCAGAUGGGACCAUCUAGUUGCAGUAAAAGAAGCUCAGGGCUUCCACUGAUUCUACAUUAUGGUAAGUUAUAUAGUUAUUUCCUUAUAUAUUAAAAUGUAAUAAUAAUAGAAAUAAAGUACACAGUAAAUGUAAUGCACUUGAAUUAUCCUGAAACCAUCCCCAUGCCACCCCCCUGAUUCAUGGAAAAAUUGUCUUCCACAAAACUGAUCCCUGCUGCUCUGUGGUAUCAGUUUGCUUUCUUUCCUACAUAGCCAUUAUUUGUAAGUAAAUUAAUGUCCUCUCCAGCAACAGAUGUUGGUUGCUAUCAUUAACAUAGUAGGUGUUUGCAAGGCUUUUUUUUUAUGACGAUGAUGAUGGUAAUGAUGAUAAAUAUAGUGUAUGAUAUUAUGCAGAUGUAGAUACUCUCAUUUUUUUCCUGUUGUUAAUGAGGGAAUGUUUUUGCAUUGCAAACAGUGAGGACAGAAACUAUGUCAGUGUCUGUCUAAAUUGCUGCGUGGAGUCUCACAACAGACAGGACUUUAAUCGCCAACAGUGUGGUAUAUCUGUCGAGUGGAGUAGAGGAAGGGCUAGAGCCCUGGAGUUCAAGUGUAAUCCCCACACCACCUGAGAGUCCAAGGGAGCAUGAGGCUAUUUGAUACCUUGGUUUACUCAUCUCUAAAACAAGGUCCCUGUGUCAAAUGGGCCAGAUGAUCUCCAGAUCUCUCACUGACCAGUGGGGCUUGCCGUCCACCCUCUAUUUGACAGGUGAGGGCACCGAUGGCACUGACUUGGGCAAUGUUUAAUUGACUUGCUCAAGGUCAAGAUCAGCAGAGCUAGAAGUAGAAUCCAGUUCUCUGGCACCAAGUCCCGUGCUCUUUCCACUUCCCCGCUCAUAAUUUCAGGGUGGUCCGAGGCAGUAUAAGAGGCUAGUGAAAUGUUAGAGUUUUGAAGAAAACUGAAGUAGUAAGGCAGUGUUAAGAAAAACAGGGAAUCCUCUAGGUUUGGUCAGAGUUCAUCCAGGACUUGCCCAGAAUGCUUGAGCUCCCUCAGGAACACCUGGCUGUGAUCCACAGCCCUCCAGGUGUCUUUUCAUUUCUCCCCCAACCAUUCAGAGGAACUGCUGGCCUGAGGAUGCCCCAGGAACAGCCCCACUCCUGGCCUGUGGGGAGUUACCCCUGAACAGGAGCAGCUCCAAACCCAGCUGUCUAGAGCGGGACCAGCCUCAGGGCUGGGAGGAGGGCUGGGGCCCAAGCAAUGCGGUCUGCGCUUUGUUUCCCUUGCCGUGGCACUGCCAAGACCUGCAGUACACGCCCCCAGUCAUCGUUUUGACAACCCCAAUAUCUCCCACACUUCCCUCUGUCUCCAGAGCCUUUUUCUGAGGCUAUUUAUUACUAAGUACAGAACAGUCUAUAAAUAAUUUUCAUGUCAAAAGAAAAGUACCUGUGCUAGAGAGUUACAAUGAUUCCAAUUAAUUUUAUGACCAUUUUUAUCAUUGGAGUUUGGAAACUUGGAGUGGAAAUCCAGCAAUAUUGCCAACUUUUGCCUGGUAUGAGUGGAGUGGCAUUUUUAUUUCACCCUGUAUGCCAGCCCCUUGCCACUGUCUUCGUUUCUUCAGUUUUCUUGAAGCAGUCAUUUUGAAGAGAUAAACAAUGUAUGUAAAAAAUUACAUGGAACCUGCAAACACACUUGAGACUAAAAUGCGGAGCUGCUUCUAGAUAUGCAUCCUAGUGAGCCACUGAAAGUACUUUGAUGAUUUAGUUGCCGCACAUAAAUAAAAUAUUCAAUUAAAUUAAAAAACAUACUUUUUUUAUUUUUUUAUUUUUUUAGUAUUUAUUGAUCAUUCUUGGGUGUUUCUCCGAGAGGGGGAUUUGGCAGGGUCACAGGACAAUAGUGGAGGGAAGGUCAGCAGAUAAACAAGUGAACAAGGGUCUCUGGUUUUCCUAGGCAGAGGACCCUGCGGCCUUCCGCAGUGUUUGUGUCCCUGGGUACUUGAGAUUAGGGAGUGGUGAUGACUCUUAACGAGCAUGCUGCCUUCAAGCAUCUGUUUAACAAAGCACAUCUUGCACCGCCCUUAAUCCAUUUAACCCUGAGUGGACACAGCACAUGUUUCAGAGAGCAGGGGGUUGGGGGUAAGGUUAUAGAUUAACAGCAUCCCAAGGCAGAAGAAUUUUUCUUAGUACAGAACAAAAUGGAGUCUCCUACGUCUACUUCCCUCUGCACAGACACAGCAACAAUCUGAUUUCUCUAUCUUUUCCCCACAUUUCCCCCUUUUCUAUUCGACAAAACCGCCAUCGUCAUCAUGGCCCGUUCUCAAUGAGCUGUUGGGUACACCUCCCAGACGGGGUGACUGCUGGGCAGAGGGGCUCCUCACUUCCCAGACGGGGCAGCCGGGCAGAGGCAUCCCCCACCUCCCUCCCGGACGGGGCGGCUGCCUGGCGGAGGGGGGGCUUCACUUCACACAUGGGGCGGCUGCCGGGCGGAGGGGCUCUUCACUUCUCAGACGGGGCGGCCGGGCGGAGACGCUCCUCACCUCCCAGAUGGGGUGGCGGCCAGGCAGAGGCACUCCUCACAUCCCAGAAGGGGUGGCGGGGCAGAGGCACUCCCCACAUCUCAGACGAUGGGCGGCCGGGCAGAGACGCUCCUCACUUCCUAGAGGGGAUGGCGGCCGGGAAGAGGUGCUCCUCACUUGCCAGACUGGGUGGCCGGGCAGAGGGGCUCCUCACAUCCCAGACGAUGGGCGGCCAUGCAGAGACGCUCCUCACUUCCCAGACGGGGUGGCGGCCCGGCAGAGGCUGCAAUCUCGGCACUUUGGGAGGCCAAGGCAGGCGGCUGGGAGGUGGAGGUUGUAGCGAGCCGAGAUCACGCCACUGCACUCCAGCCUGGGCAACAUUGAGCACUGAGUGAGGGAGACUCCGUCUGCAAUCCCGGCACCUCAGGAGGCCGAGGCUGGCAGAUCACUCGCGGUUAGGAGCUGGAGACCAGCCCGGCCAACACAGCGAAACCCCGUCUCCACCAAAAAAAUAGGAAAACCAGUCAGGCGUGGUGGCGCGCUCCUGCAAUCCCAGGCACUCGACAGGCUGAGGCAGGAGAAUCAGGCAGGGAGGUUGCAGUGAGCUGAGAUGGUGGCAGUACAGUCCAGCUUCGGCUCGGCAUCAGAGGGAGACCGUGGGGAGAGGGAGACUGCGGGGAGAGGGAGACCGUGGGGAGAGGGAGACUGUGGGGAGAGGGAGAGGGAGAGGCAAAAACAUACUUAAGAAAAAUAUACGCACACAUUUUAAGGCUGCUUGGGGAAAUGUAUCCACUAUAAAGACAUGUACAUUUUUUAAGUUUUUACCCUACCUCAUUCCAAAAGGAUUCAAGAUCACUUUGGGACAGAUACUGGCAGAUAAAACAAUCUGAACUCAAAAUGUAAUGGCAGAAUGGCUUCCUUACUACACAGGCCUCCCAUUUCCACAGCUACAGCUACAGCUACAGCUACACCCCCAGUUUCAGAACCAAUACUCUUCUUAGCCAGAGAGAAUUCAAACCACUUCCCUCAUUUGGGAGUUGGGUGGAGCAAUGUCAAGUCAUCUUGAGGAUGUUCUGCUCAGAUGUGGUGCAUUAGUAACCAGGCCCUUAAUCCAACUCCUCUCCCUGAGCCUUCAGUGAACUUUGUCUCUGGGUGCCAGUCUUGUCCCCCAAGGCCAAGCCCAUCCUCAAAACCUGUGUAAUUUCCUUGAUCCUCCAGAUUUGGGAACCUUCCAUCCUCCCCCUAGCCCAGUUGGUAGUAGGGGUUCUCCCCUGAACCCCAAUCCCUCCUCCUAAGGUGGAAGGGCAAAAAUGUGGACUUCGAAAUCAACAUAUCUGGGAGUGACUCUACAGUGUACCUUUUUACUGUCAUUAAAACUUUGACAACUUACUUCAAUUUUCUUUAGAUAGGAGGAAUAAUAAUACCAAUCUCAGAGAUUUUGGUGAGGAUGAAAUGAGGUAACACAAAGUGCUUCAGACAGGGUAUCAUAUUUAGUGCAUGUCAAUAUUGUUAUUACCUCUCCCCAAGCAUACUGAACACCAACCAUCUAUCUCCCAUGUCUCACCAUAUUAACCUGAAAACAAGCUUCCCUGCAGGCCAGAUCUACUCAGCCCCCUUUCUGCCUGCAGAAUACCCUCUAGUACCUCUUAGUGGACUUCCUUCCCUCUCCCUGUCCUACUCUCUACUCCUCAUCACAGAAUCUGAUUUUGCACACUGAAGGGCCUGCCUCACAUUGUCCACCUACAGCCAGGUGUGUUCCACAUCCAGGUGGGUCAGUCCAGACUUUCCCACAUUCUCCACCACCACCUCAGCCCAGGGUCUGAUGGAAGUGAAGAUAAAACUGAUGCGUAAGAGUUACAAGAGUGGACAGUUUCUUUAUCAUUACUGCAUUUCUCUUUUGUUGGAAAGACCAAUCCUUUAAAUGUUUCAUGACUUUUACCCUUAUUUUUUUUUCUUUAUUCUAAAACUAGUAGCUACCAUGAUGAACAAGAUAGACACAGUACCUGCCUUCAAUUUGUGUAUGCUUUAGUAAGAGAAUACUAUACUGGACAGUAUAUUACACAUUUGACAUUCCAAGUCUCAAAAUACCCAGUUUUAACUUUGUACUUUACAUGAUUCUUCCACUUGGGAAAGUUGCUUAAACCAUCUGCACGUCAUUUUCUUCAUCUGAAAAAUGGGAAUAAUGCUAGCCUCCACCUAUGGCUUUGCAAGCAGCCUCAGCUCUCCCCAUUGGCUGGUCUCCUUAAUGUAGUACACAAAUGGUACAGCUAUAGGAAGAUCCCUGAAUUAGAUAAUUCACUUUAAAUACUUAAAAAGUAACACUGAAAGGCUGACACAUUGUAAAUUUCUAGCAAUAACAUUAUUAAUUGUAAUAGUGGAAUGAGACUAAUGAGAACACAUUGGGAAGACAGAUUAAUAUCAUUCAGAGCCUUAUAUAUUUUGCAGCAGCUUUGUCUCAUUAGAAACAUGUUUUCAGUCGAUAUUAAAUGUAAGAAAACAGCUUUCUUCUUAUCACCAGCUCAUUCUUCAGAAGCCACUGAAUCAUGUGAGAUGUCUCUUUCAUUUUUGACCCCUGCUUCAGCACUCCUUCUAAAAAGAUAGUAAAUGAGCAUGUUACAUUUGCUGCUGCAGUUAACUACUGUCUGUGAGAUGCAGCAAGAGAUUAUCUGAGAGCAUGUGCGUAAAUGAUAGAUUGCCUCGAGCCUAUUUAUACAUGCAGCAGUAAUGAGGAAAAGUUGAAGGAGGCAUGAAGGAUGGGAGGGAGGGAAGGAGAGAGAUGAUGCCAGAAUGUGCAGAGUGUAGACAGAGGAAGAGAGUCAAAGAAGGAAAAAUAAAGAGAGGUGAACAGCAGGACUAGAAACAUGUAAGCAGAGAUGGUGGGAGGGGGCAUCAGUAGGUAAAAGGAAAGAAGGGAACAGAGAAAACUCAUUAGCAACCAACAGAAAAGGCAGAAUUUUGAGAAAACAAAAUGCAUCAGGCAGAUUGGGAAGAAAGUAGAAUGAAAGAAAUGAAAACAGGAAUCAAGGUGAAUAGAAUCCAAUGCCACAGUGGGAAACAUACAUUAUUAGAUGAUGUCGAUUUUAUGUAAACAAGGGAGCAAAGGUUUUGUCUGAUAGAAAUUUCUGAACUCCUUUGAAGUCACUACCAUAAGCAUUCCACAGGCAUUCUAUUCCUUCUUUGCAUUGUAUUUAAAAUGGGCACACUAGGGAAAAUUACAGAGUGUCUUUAUCAUAAGUUGAACUCCUAAGCUAUCACAUUUCAAAUACUGAAACACUAUCAUAUAAUAUUAAAGGAAAUUAUAGUAUGAAUAGAGACAAAACUGAAGUUAUUCUGUUAAUAAGACUAUUUCCAUCAUCUUUCCUUAGGAUGCUUUAUCCAUAGUGGCAUGUUGGUCUUAUAACAUCCCUUUAGGAGAAAUUGAUGGGCAUAGCAUGGUUUUUAUUUCACCAAACAUGGUUAAAGGACUAAUAAGAUAAUCCACAAAUUAGUCACAGAACUAGGGACAUCAUCCAAGUUUCUUGUUCCAUUUGUACAAUGAUUGCCCACUCUGUUCAUCCUACAGAAACAAAUGAACCAGGGAUUAAACACACCCAGGUGGGAGUCUGGACUCCCUGAUGUUAUAACUUUAUAAACUGGAGCAACUCUGAUGUUCUUUGUUAGGUUUCUCUUUCUAUAAAAUGGAGAUACUGCCACUUUUUUCCCCCAGGAUUAUUAUAACUAUUAGGGAUAAAAUAUAUAAAGUGUUUGAAACAGGUAGAUAGUCGACACAUUGUAGCAAUUAUCAUUUUCAUGCAACAGCAAAUAGUCAUACAUAUCUUUACAGUAAAAAAGAAGUAUUAAUAUCAUUGUAUUCAUCAAAAAGGUGGGGGAGACAGCAAGAUUAAAUUAGAGCAGGAAAGGAAAAUAAUGGAAAAGCUUGCUAGAGUGGUUGUAUCCUAUAGUAAAAUGGAAAUGUAUUCCUGUAUUGCCUCUGAGUCAGUGUACCUCAGUGAAAACAAGUACAGAAAUGAAAUAAAUUCAACUGCAGCCUCAUGAAGUACUAUUAAAAUGGAGGUUUGGCGUCCCUCAGAAAAUGUCUUCAUCUGUACCUGAUGGUUGAGGUAACGAAUUAAGGGGGAUCCAGACUAUAAAAAGAAGAGUCUCGAAGGUUGAAGCCUGAUUUUUUGACAUUCGAAAACCUAAGAAUCAGCAGCGGUCAUUCUCCCUCAGACUUCAUCACUCAAACUUAAAGCCUUUCUGGAGCCCAAGGACACAGAGACCUCUAAGCUGUGUAACCAGGACAUUGGACAAAUGUGGUUCGUAAGAUUAGGUCCUAAAGCAACAUUAUUUUGUUUUUCACUGUUUCUUUAAAUUAUUCAAUGGGAUCCAGUUCUUCCCCUACCCCAGGAUGAAUAUUUGGGUGAGGCCAUAACUUUUCUGUUCAUCCUUAAGGAAUACAAACAGUCUUAAUUUGCUAAUUUGUAAGUCCAACUCCAUGUCAUAGUCAAAACUCGGAGUGUGAUUUACAGUUAACGCAUUUUCUCUCUCCCAGCUUCUGUGUGCUGCAGUUGAUGACGGGAGGUGUGUCUGGCUCCUUCUCUCUCCCUCACAUAAGGUUUCUCCUUCUCCUCCCACAGCUGAUGAAUUGUAGGUUCUGACCUCUGCAAGGUUAGAGUUUAGGGAAGCACUGGAAAGUCCUUACUUGUCUGACACUGUAAUGAGCUGGUGUCACACUCUCUGAUCUUCGCAGACGUUUCAACCUGGCACUUUCUCUUCAUAUGCACUUUGGUAGGAUCUUCUGAGACACCCAUUGCUUGUGCUGUCUCACUUGCAGUUCCUCCACAUGGGGGAAAUGACACCCUAGCUAUUACAGUGGAUCAGUUUGAUGAGAGGGAAUUGCAUUGCGGCGUUUUAUGUGUUGUUUUAUUUUUGUGGAUAGCAGAAUAGUUGUGUGUACCAUUGCCAUCUCAGUUAACAAUGUAAAAAGCACAAAAAUAAGUCAAGUAAAUGAAAAAAAUCAAGAUAAAUGAAUCUGAACAGAGAUACUACUGCUUGGAGUUAGUUCAGUGAAGAACUUAUCACAUAUUCUGAUUUACAAGAGGCUCUGAUGAUAAUGGCACAUUGCCAGUCCUCUACUCUCCCCUUUCUUUGGUGAAAUGGCUCACCUUUCCAUGAACUCUGUUUAAAGAGACACUCCAGAGGAGUCUGUACUCUGGAGACAUCAAGGAAAAGGAGAUGAAAAGGAGAGCAAGAUCUAGAAAAGCAUUGUUUUGAGGCGGAAAGUUUGUGAAGAAAGGAAUGGCCAUUUGAAAAUGAAAGUUUACUCAUUUAUAUUUUAGAAAAACAAAUGAUAUUAAAUAACUACAACAAAAGAAGAAAGGGAGUGACACAUAGGUCAUUUAUUUUAAAAAUCUUUUCAGGCCGGGUGCGGUGGCUCAACCCUGUAAUCCCAGCACUUUGGGAGGCCGAGGCGGGCGGAUCACGAGGACAGGAGAUCGUGACCACGGUGAAACCCCGUCUCUACUAAAAAUACAAAAAAUUAGCUGGGCGCAGUGGCCGGCACCUGUAGUCCCAGCUGUUCAGGAGGCUAAGGCAGGAGAAUGGCGUGAACCUGGGAGGCGGAGCUGCAGUGAGCCAAGAUUGCACCACUGCACUCCAGCCUGGGCGACGGAGCGAGACUCCGUCUCAAAAAAAUAAUAAAAAAAAUCCUUUCAAACUACUGUUAUUUUGCAACUAAAAAUUAUAGAACAUUAUGUAUCAAGCUCUAAAUUCUCACCAGGGCUGAGCCACAUGAAACUCCCAUUUUAUAGAUAAAAAUGUUCAAAUAUUGUCAGUAUCAUAUGGCUUAGAAUCUUAACCUCAUUUACCACAACUACUGAAUUCUUUCUUGUAGUCUAGAAAUUUAAAAACUUAAAUUAGGUACUUUAAGAAUCCCAUGCCGAGCGCAGUGGCUCACACCUGUAAUCCCAGCACUUUGUGAGGCCGAGGCGGGUGGAUCACGAGGUCAGGAGAUCGAGACCAUCCUGUCUAACAUGGUGAAACCUCAUCUCCACUAAAAAUACAAAAAUUUUAGCCGAGCGUGGUGGUGGGCGCCUGUAGUCCCAGCUACUCGGGAGGCUGAGGCAGGAGAAUGGCGUGAACCCGGGAGGCGGAGCUUGCAGUGAGCCAAGAUCGCACCACUGCACUCCAGCCUGGGUAACAGAGUGAGACUCCGUCUCAAAAAAAAAAAAAAAAAAAAAAAAAUUUCAUGAAGAUCCUAAGCUUGAGAUGAAGGUAGUGUCUUUCUUCUCUCUUCAUCCCCUGUAACACCCAGCCCACAACAGUUGCUGAGAGAAUACUUAUUGACUUCUAUCACAAGCUCAGAGUAAUUUUGAACUUGCACCGUCAUUAUUAGCCACAAACGUUGCAGAAUUAGAUUCUUAUCAUUGAGCUUUCCCUUAAUACCCAAAGUGGAGGAUACAAGUUUUAAAAUCUUACAUAUACUCGAUGACUAUUAAAAAAAAAACUUUACCCUUUUUUCCCCUCUAAAUUGCUCAGGGAACGGGCAGAGGGAAGAAAGGUGGGGAGGUAAUUCUCACGGGGCAAAGAGGCUCAGCUCUGGAGGGAAGAGGUGGAAGCCAGCCUCCAGCCCCAGGCACCUACCAAAGCCAGGGAGCCGGUUAACAUGAGAUCUGCUUGACUGCGACGUCACAGGGGGACAGGUGCAAAAACAGAAUAUGUAAAGGAAUUGUAUGCUAAUUCUGUCCUCUCAGUGUCUUCGAAGAAAUUAUUUCCUGGCGAUUUGUUCAGCACUUAAAAAAAAAUGUCCAUAUACCCGCACCUCACCAAUCUACCCAUUCUCUUUGGUGUUUUUCUUAUCUGAUUGGAAAUUUCCUAGUACAUGUAGGGCUUUGUUCUAAGAAUAGGUGAACACAGCUGGAAUUGCAGUGUCAUCUGUUGCAUAUUUGGAGAGACUUUCAAAAAAACUUGACCUUAACCUGCUAACUUCAACCCAGAAUUCCAGACAGAUAUUUGGACCUUCUAAAAUCAUAAACAUUUGAUAUUUAUAUUCCUGGACUAAUUUUUUAAGCAAAAAAUUUGCAUCUGGCCUUUUGCAAUCUUCCAAAGGAAGUUUUUCAGAUACGUCUGGGGGUGUGAUUUCUUAAUAGAAUAAAACUGCCAUGGUUUUAUAAUAUGCUGCUAUAUGGUGCUAGAAACCUCUCCAAAACACCCUCAAAUUUAUCAACACCAAAAUCCCCAAAGAUACAAAGAUGAUAUUAGCAUUUUAUUAUAAAUGCAUUUGGGAUCCUCAAUAACUUGAAAGCCUUCUAUUUUAGCAUUAGAAUGAAACAUAAUGCUAAUUAAUAAAUAAGGAGCUAAGCAUGGUGCCAAAUGAAAUAAAUAUUUACUGGAAAUAACCAAAAUGACUUCACUGCAGCAGAAAGGUCCUAAAACUGUACUCAGAAGAAUGCUGGCUGUUUCUGUGUUUUCACUAACACAUGCUGAAUACCAUGUCCCACUCUUCAUACCUGGGAGGGAGCAGGGCAAGGAUGACCCUUACUGCGAAGGAGCAGUCACACAGUCAAACAGUAUUAAAUAAGUAUUUUAUGAUCAAUACCCUUAAAACCCCAAGAGAAAUUUUAAAACUUAAAUUGUCUGAAGCUUAGCUGUACAGCUCCCAAUUAAAUGAGCGAACUGUGUUUUUAAAUACCCAUGUCCUACUCAAAAUUCCCCAUAGCUUUUCUUUUAAAAGCUAUAAAAUGUGUUACUGGUGACAGAAUUCAGCUUAAUAAGUUUCAGUAGGUUUUGAUAGUUCAUUCACACUUUAGCUUAUAAAAAGUGUAGGCAAGUAAGCAAAAUCAUUUUUCCUGUCUCCUGCAUUAUUGGAAAAGGUACAGAAUCCAGCUGCAUUUCAUUAAAGUUGUUUUGGAAAGUUGAAGACAGCCCAUGAGGAAAAGAGGACUCAAAAUUAAAUACUUGGAACCUGAGGUUAAACAUUGCACAUGGCUUUAUGUGCCUCUCUCCCCUUAUAUUUGGAUGACAAAUGACUUCAGGCCUCUGCCGACCUAAGGAUUUGUCGUUGAUGAUUCAACAAGAAGAACUACUUAGACUUGUUUAGGAUUCAUGGUGAACAGGCAGUUUCCCAUUCAUUCUAUUAUAUAAUGGUCACUCUUAGGUCACAUAUACACCAAAGGGGCCCUGGCUUCAGAGGAACUUAAACCUUUGUAAGCUCUUUUAUGAGUCUAGUCCUAUUGGAAAGCAUUUGAUUCCACUGUCAGUCACCUUGUGACUCUUUUGUUUCCCUGAUAAAUAAUUAAAAGUGGGUUGGAUCCUCAUAGCAGUGUUGAUAGAACACCCUUGACAAUGAUGGCUUUGUGGCACAGUGUUGAGGUCUUUAUUUUAUAGAGCAGCAGAAAAAGUUCCUAUUAAAGACAACACUCAAAUUCUUCACUUUGUUAUGUCAGUGAUUUUAAUAUUGUAAAUGUUCAACUUCAACCCUUUUGUUUCACUAUGAAUAUAUCCAAUAUAGCCUCCAGAGUUUUACAAAAGGUGCCCUUGGAGUAACUCACCCACUGGGGUUAUAUUUACCACCCUAGUGGCUUCCUGUUUGGGAACCUGGCAGGGGCAAUGAGUAGGCUUGAGAUGCUUUUUGAACAAUCCACCAUUCUCUUACAUUCUCCUUCAUGUACACAGGUACUCCAACUGCUUUGCAGAGAAGUGGUAAACUAAUAACCCUAUUUACUCAGUCAAAAACUAUGUGGGAGUCAAUAUUUGGGGUGAGGCUUUCUCUUCAGAAAAGAAAUGUUUGGCAAAACAGCCUAAAUUCUCCAGGAUAGAAGAGAUUGAUGGAGCAUCUAUCUUAAGAAGGGUGUAGGCAAGGAUACUAGGUUAACUCCUAAAACAAAUAUAAAUGUUUCUUUUCCAUAUUCCAGGUAAUGAAACCAACACGAGAAAGGAGAGGGUUUGUCACUCUAGUUCCUCUUGAUUCUUUCCAGCAGAGGGCACCAUUUUCAUUAUCUAGAUGGGUUUCACAGUUUUAGACAUGGGAAUUGUUAGGUUCUAUAAAUUAGAAUAGGCAAAUUACUGAAGAGGGCCUGGAAACUGAGCUCUCAGCUCCUGGAACUGGGAACAGACCACUUUAUUCUGUAGAUAAAGAAAAAUAGCACUUGUCUAGAAAAUGUAGGCUGUUCAAGCAGUUUAUUUAUUUAUUUUUUAUUUAAGUAUAUUGUAAGACCCACUACAACAAGCAGCUUAAUUUAGAUCUUGGUAUUUGAGAUAAAUCCCCACUAAACUAAGGUAAAUACAUCUCCUUUGAACAUUUGUGCAUACAUAUAUACACACGCAAUUACAGCUUUUAAAUUAUUUUGACUGCUUUAAAAUGUGGCUUUCCUUCUCUUGGAAACACUUAACACAAGAGUCAUAAAUAUCACCACAAUUCUCUGCUGUACUGUGAUGUUUAGUUGUAUCCGUCCUUAAAAUCUUAUUCUAUGGGUGUUGGAAAUGACAAAUAUAUACAUUGAACGCUGAAUUUGGUUUUAUCAGAUCUGGUACUCUCAUGUGGCUAGGCAAAGAGUUAUCGUGCCCCUCUGUUCCUUUAUUUGUGCACUUUGUAGAUUAUGUUAUCUGGCAAGCAUCCAGGUCUAUUGUGAAGGCACUGAAACAAUACCUUGUAUAGGUUGAACCAUAACACUGUCAAAAGCCAGCACAACAAACCAAGGGACCAAGUAGUUCACAUUGGAACUCAAUAAAAAUAACCUCUCUGAGAGGUUAGAGAAUCAUGAUUGUAAAUAAUGCCCACUGGAAAUCCAUGAGAAUGGAUUUUCUGAAAAUAUUUACUGCUCCAGGUGGAUUAUUAUUUUGACUACUUAUGGCAUGUACAUCUCCCAAAAUAAAUUGGGAUGAAGUAUAGAUAAAGGUUUUUAUUUCUUCCCCAGUGGAUUGCUACAUGUGCAAACUUAAAGGUCUGCUGAGUAAUUAUGGACACUAGAGAGCAGUAGAGGAGUGUCUGAGCACAUAGCUGGUAGAAAAUCAACAUGCUUCAAAACAGUAUCAGGCAUAUUCUCUUAAGGUGAUAUUCAGUUUCCACUGACAGUGGAAGACAAUUUGAACUAUCUUAUAAAUGAAUCAAUUUUUAGAGAUUGGAUAAAUAACAUCCAAACAAUAAGCUAUCAAUAGGAAUGCUAGUAUUUAUACUGAUAAGUAGUUUAUUAUAAGUCAAAACUGCUUACUUUGGAGUAGAAAAAUUUGGUAACAAAUUCUGCAUAAGAUUUAGGUCAUCAGUAAUAGCUGUAAUUCAAAGCAGAUCUCUGACUACUUAUGUAGAAGAGUCAUCAAAAUCAGUGUGAUUUCAAUGAAUGCCUAUUUAUACCCAACAUUCAAGACAUCUGCAUCAAUUUACCAAUAAAUGUGUCUACCAUUCAUUAUGCAGUCAAACUAGCCCGUGUACAAACUACAUCACAAUUCUGAUCUGUUUCCCCUUGGCCAUAGUAACUCUACUCGGGUGAUGGAGAGAGUUACAGUGAAAAUAACCACCACCAUUAUGCUUAUGCUGUGACAGACACCAUGCAGUGCAGCCUCCAUUGUAUGGCUUCCACUUCUAGCCUCCCAUAACCACAUGUCCAAAGUCAGAAUCUUGGUUCCUUGUUCUUAUAUCUUUCCAGCUUAUAAACAGUACCAUUAUCCACCCACACCAGAAACAUAAGAGUCAUCCUUGAUCCAUUCCUCUUCCUUACUGUCCGUAAGUCCUCUUGAUUCUAAUUCUAAAAUACAUCUCAAAUCCAUUUCCUUCUUUCCAGUUCCACUGUCACAUUCUCACCUGGGCCCCCAUCAUCACAUGUCUGCACACUGUAAGAACCUCCAGCUGGUCUUUCUCCUCCCAACAGUAGUAGUGUAUUUAUAUUUGAUAACACAGACCAGAUCCUAGCAUUUCCCUGUGUGACAUCCUUCAACUGCUGCCCAUUCAUCUUGGAAUAUAAUGUAAACCCCUGGUAGUGGCUCUCUAAGCCCUGACCGUCUCUCCUGGCUCACCCUGUACCCCUUCCAAAUUCUUUUUGACUCGGGGCCUUCCUGUGUGGUGUUGCCCCUGCCUGAAAGCUGUGUGAUUUCAGGAAGUCACUUAACCUUCUGGGCCUUGAUUUUCUCCUCUAAAAUAAGGACCUUGAUCCUUUCUAGCAAUGACCUUCCUGUUUUCUUAGAAAAAAAAAUAGCAGUUCUCUUGAAUUUAUCUUCUAAUAACCCUCUACUCAGCACUGACCCUGACAUAAUAUGAAAGGUUAGCCACAGGCCCAUUGGAAAAUAUUUUCCAAGUAUAGUAUAGAACUAUAAAAUGCUUUGAAACUGAGACAUACAUGUUAACCAGCAAUGUUUUCAAUUAAUAGAGGGAUGUGUAUACCCUGUGAGAAUGCUUAAAGCCUAAAAUUAAAGCAGGGCAGGAGACUUCAUCUUUCUUAGAAAGCAAAUUUACUGUUCUCUCACUAGUUUCUGUCUGAAUUUACCAGCUCCAUGUGAGUUUGUAUGUUCAUUGGCAUUCUAACCAUCCUUUAUUAUAAGUGCAUUUUCAAGGUUUAUACUAUUCUCAUCAGCAGCACACUCUUGUCAAGUUUUUAAUUUCAGAUUGUCAGACAUCCAAACUAGAAUUGUUCCAUUGCCUAUAGCAGAUAAUAAAUAAUUAGAUGCUCUUAAAUCAGUGGACCGCAGAAAAUGAAGGUGAAUUUUUAAAAUUCAGUUUAUUUAUAAACUGAGCCAACCCCAUGCCAGUUCAAUCCAGUUCUGUGCAUUUUGCUGAGUGUCUUCCAGAUGCCAGGCACUACACCAAUAUAGGCUAUGUAAUAAGCAAAUGCUGGGCCCAGCUCUCUAAGAACUCACAGUCCAGCAGGAAGAUCUAUAUGCAAAAAUAUCAUGUCAGAAACCUGGUGAAGUAAUAGAAGAAGGCGCUGUGUGCUUUGGGGUAACAAAGUGCUUCUGUCACCAUGGAGGGAUCAGACAAAGUGUCAUGAGUAAAUAAUAUUUACCUGUCAAAGAAGAAAACAGUGUCCCAGGAAGAGGAUUCUGGUAUGCAGAGAAACCAGAAGUGCAUCAGCAGUGUCCUUUGGGGAAACAACUGAAAUACAAAAGUGUCUGUGGCCAGAGACAAAGCUGGAAAGAGAUGCAGGCACCAAGUCAUGAAGGACUUUGUAUGUCUCGUAUUCUCUCCAAAAAAUUUGAGCUGUAUCCUGAAAUACUAAUAAUAACAACAUGAGCUAACUUGGGGGCCUCACUAAAACCACUUUACAUGAUCUAACUCAUAUAAUGCUCAACAGCUGAUGAGGUUUCAGCCCAGGUAAGCCACUGUUUGAGUCAUGCUCUGAACUACGGUUAUUCCACCUCCAAGUGAAAAGGAGCCAUAGAAAUUGUAUGACCUUGGGCAAAUUACUCAACACUGAACCUUCUUCCAUCAUCUGUAAACCAGGAAUAAUCAUAGUGCCUGCCUCAUAGAAUUGCUGUAAGAACUAAACAAAUUAACAAAUGUAAAAUGCUUGGGUAGCAUUGUGCAUGGCAUGUGGCAUGUAACUGCCGUUAUUAUUAUCAUCUUCAACAUUAUCAUUUCCAUUAAUUUUUAAGAUUUUAAGAAAUGGAACACCAUUACCAUGUUUGCAUUAAAAGAUGACUAAGAGGGCAAAUGAAGGAAGGCAGGUGGCAAGGCCAUUAUAUUGCCAACCCCAAGGGGCACCAUUCACUUUGUAGUCAGUGUAAAUGACACAGUGCCCCCUUGGACCUGUGCUGUGCAAUGGCUCUGAGCAGAACAAGACAAGAGGUAAUCCAGAGGUGAUGAGAACCUAAAUGAGGGGAACAGAGAAGAAACUGGUGACAGAUAUUGGGGAACAAGAGAUCUCAUGGGUAAGGACAAUAAAGAGGGACUUGAUUAACUGCUAGGUUUCUGGCCUGGGUAGGUGUGCAGAGGGGAAAUAAGAGGGGUGGGGAAUCAACUCGGAUUAUUUUAUGUCUCUGGAUAUGUGUCUCUAACUGCUUUCCAAAGGGAAAAUAAACAUGAUUUCAGAUUAGUGAUUUUGUCCUAUUAAGUGUGUUUCAUCCUUUUAUGAGUGUAAAUAAUUGGGAUUUACUGAGUUAAUCCCAAUUAACUCAAACUGUGUUCCUAAUAACAUAGCCCAGUGCAGUUCAGUGCCAGGAUAAAUGUCAGAAUCCUAUGUUGAUUUUGUGUUAUUGCAGUCUUCUGUUUGGCAAGACUGACCUUGUUAUUUCUGAAUUAAUGAUUUCAAUCACCCAAGACACCUUUUCAGUGAAAUACGGUACAUAAAAAUGGAGUCUCCUAAUAGUUGUGAAAAAGCACUUCAUUUUAUUAAUAUAUAUAUAUUUGAAAUACUCAUCACAGGGCAUGUAAGUGUGAACUUUUAAUGACACAGAAGAAAAAAUAUUUGUAUAUGGAUCUUUUUGUAAAGACAAGCUCAGAGCACCCUCAAAUAGAAGAGAGAGAAAAGAGUGGGUUGUGUCAUUGCAUCAGCCCCUAGAAAACCUGCACCGCUGGUGUAUUAUUCACACCCAUCUGUAGAGGUCUCUUAGGAGUCUUGGGAGUCCCUUGGGAAAAGCCUCCUGGGAACAGGCAGUUAGAGUAUGGCAGGAUCAUUUUCUUAGCCUGUUUUGGGUCCAAUUAUGUAUUUUCUAUUUUAUCUUGCUCUUAACUACUCCCCCCCCCAAAAAAAGGCCUGGUGUGUUGGCUCAUGCUUGUAAUCCCAACACCUUGGGAGGCUGAAGAGAGAGGGUCACUUGAAGCCAGGAGUUCAAGACCCCUGGACAAGAUAGCAAGACCCCAUCUCUACAAAACAACAAUAACAAACCCAGUCCAACAGGUUACACUGGCUAAACACAUUUUUCUUAGGGAUUUAAUUUUUUUCCCUGCUUUACCUUAUAUGUGAUACUUAUCAAAUAUGCCACAUUUUUAGUAUUGCUUCACUCUUAGGGGGCCAGAGUUGUGAAUGCCUUGAUUCUAUAUUCUGGGGCUUGCUCUGUAAAGCAUACAUUUUACCUAAGAUCAAUGUCACAGGUAAGUUUAUCUACUGUUCCUUUCUUUUUUUUUUCUUCAUUUUUUAAAGCAAAACAUGCCUCUUUAUUUUUCCAAAACAACUAAUCACAAUGAACAUCCAAUAUUUAGGAAAUCAAUCUAAAAACAAACCUUAAGGAAAUAAACCAUCUGUAUUAUUUUAUAAUAACAGUAAUAACUACUAUUUGCUGAGUCCUAAUCAUUGCCAAGUGCUGCAUACUUCACAUGUAUUACUGAAAUGUAAUAGUCACAACAACCCUGAAAGAUACAUUACUUCAAUUUUAUAGAUGAGGAGGUUGGGCUAAGAUAUACAUAAUUCAGGCCUUACUAGCAGAUGCUAAUUAGAAUGCUUGUUGGAAAUGCCUAGGGGGUCAUCAGAGAGUAGCAUCAAACACUGGGAGAACAGGGCCAGCAUCCUGCAGAAUUCUGUUUAGACCUGCGAGCACAGUCCCUUGCUCUGGGAGUGACUUUCUGUGUUCACAGCUUCUCUGUUGGGCCUGCUGUCCUCCAAGCUCCAGAUUCUGUAUCUUCCUCACUUAUGAUGACUGUUUGCUUACCCUGCUGCCCUCUCCACAAUUCUCCUUUCAUUCCAUGCUUCACCUUCUCCACAAGUAAUUAACAAGCACUUUCUACAUGCCAGCAACUGCUCCAAGGACUGGAGAUACAGCAGUGAACAAAACAGUCUAUUUUGUUUAAAUCUCUGUUCUGUGGAGCUGUUGGGCACAGACAGAAAAUAAACAAGUAAUAAAAUCACCCUGAAUCUUACCCUUUCAAUCUCAUACUUGACUCCAGGCUUCUAACCAAACACCUGUCAAAAACGUGGAUGGGCUCUUUUCUCAUCUGCCGUAGACGAAGUCUGUGGCAUAGAUGAAGUCUCUUCAUCCUUCUUAGGCUGUAGGAAUUCAUUGAAAGAAGAGCCCUGGCCUCUGUGUUCCUUACUCAUAUACCUGAAAAAUGAGCAAGGCUGUAGGAACUGCUAGCUCCUCUGUAACAAUUUUCCUCUUUAUUAUAUGUUCAUAUUCCUGAUAACUAGAGCACGAGAGAAUCUAGCCAGCCAUUCAGUCUUUGUUCCUGAAUACUGUCUGCCACAGAUACUUCCAUUUUUAACUGAAUAGAAUAAUCUAGAAGGAAACGUAAUACCCUCUUUUUUAGUCAUUCCUUGCCAGAUGCCUGUAUCUUUCUUCUGGCCUAUAGUCUGACCCCUUGAGCUCAGAGGAUCCCAAGGGGCUACUGUAGCCAGUCUCUGAUAAUACUGUUUUGUCCCUCUUCCCAUGAAGUUCUUGCCUACAGGAAAGGAGUAUGACUGCCAGCCCUGACCCCCUUGACCUUAGAGUGGAAUGAGGUAGAACCUUAAUAUUCUUAGAAAGGAUGUCCUAAGCUCUUAGCAAUUGUUCAGAUUUAGAAAUGGUGCUGUAACACAUAAUUUCUCCCAUAAAGUGCAGUCAAGUGUAAGUGACCUCUUCAGAACCUUAAUGAUUCUAUAUUAAACAAAAACAAUUGAAUUUCUUAUAAAAAUCAUCAGUUAUGUACAACUUCUUAAUAUUCUCUCCACCUCCAGUGACAGUACAAGGAGUCAACUCUCCCGUGGGAGCAAUUGUUCAAAGUAGAAUUUGCCACCUCAAGGAAGUUAGAGUGAUACGGGUAACAAUAAUAACAGGAAUAUGAGCUGGCCUGACACAGAGCUCACUAUGUGUCAGGCUCCAUGCUGACAGCUUUACAUGUAUGACUCUUUAAAUCCUCCAACAGCCUUACAAAGUAAGUGCUAUUAUUGUCCUCAUUUUUCAGAUGAGAAAACUGAAGUAGAGAGAGGUAAAAUAACUUGCCUAACAUUAUCCAGCUAGUAAAUGGUGGAACCAGGACUCCUAUCAAGGCUGCCUGUCCUCAGAGCCAGUGCCAAAAUCUCAACUCUGUCAUCCUUCUCAAUAUGAGUGAAUAAAAAAGCUGUGAUGAGGUGUGCUGCUGAGGGCUUACUCACCUUUGAAUGGGGCUGCCACACUUGUUAUCCACAGUGGAACAUUCAAAUCAAUGCCUCAGUGAAGUGGCAGAUUGUCCCAUGUCAUAGGUGUUUGGGUCACUGGGAACAUCCGCUCCUUCAGUGUCAGGGUCGGCUGGCAUUCUGACUUCACCAAGCCUACCUGUGGCUAUAGUUCAUCCAGCCUAGUAUUUCUAGUUUGGGCUGCUGCUCCCCUUCCUCUCCACCAGAAUUUUUACUAUUUCAGGAGGAGGUGAAUCCCUGUGAGGUAGAUUUCUGAUUUUGGAGAUGAUACUUGUGAUUAAAGAGAAAGCUUGAUAGGAGGAGAGCCAGAAUUUUCCAUGACUUUAAAAGAGGAAAUAAUUUUCUGCUUCACUCUGGAAGACAAGGGAAAUGCCUCCCCUAACAAUUCCCUUUAUCAAAGUAACAUUUCACCUGCCAGGUAGGUAUUACUUCAUUUGAAUACAAUAGCAGCCUUCAGCAGCAGUAGCUAAAAUUUACUCCUAUCACUUUCUUUUUACAAAGCCUUCAAAUUUGUACACGAAUAGAAUCUUAGAAACAACCAAUUUUUUUUAUAUAUACUUUAAGUUUUAGGGUACAUGUACACAACAUGCAGGUUAGUUAC